ACAAUUGCUCUACAGCUCAGAACAGCAACUGCUGAGGCUGCCUUGGGAAGAGGAUGAUCCUAAACAAAGCUCUGAUGCUGGGGGCCCUCGCCCUGACCACCGUGAUGAGCCCUUGUGGAGGUGAAGACAUUGUGGCUGACCAUGUUGCCUCUUACGGUGUAAACUUGUACCAGUCUUAUGGUCCCUCUGGGCAGUACAGCCAUGAAUUUGAUGGAGACGAGGAGUUCUAUGUGGACCUGGAGAGGAAGGAGACUGUCUGGCAGUUGCCUCUGUUCCGCAGAUUUAGAAGAUUUGACCCGCAAUUUGCACUGACAAACAUCGCUGUGCUAAAACAUAACUUGAACAUCGUGAUUAAACGCUCCAACUCUACCGCUGCUACCAAUGAGGUUCCUGAGGUCACAGUGUUUUCCAAGUCUCCCGUGACACUGGGUCAGCCCAACACCCUCAUCUGUCUUGUGGACAACAUCUUUCCUCCUGUGGUCAACAUCACCUGGCUGAGCAAUGGGCACUCAGUCACAGAAGGUGUUUCUGAGACCAGCUUCCUCUCCAAGAGUGAUCAUUCCUUCUUCAAGAUCAGUUACCUCACCUUCCUCCCUUCUGAUGAUGAGAUUUAUGACUGCAAGGUGGAGCACUGGGGCCUGGAUGAGCCUCUUCUGAAACACUGGGAGCCUGAGAUUCCAACACCUAUGUCAGAGCUCACAGAGACUGUGGUCUGCGCCCUGGGGUUGUCUGUGGGCCUCGUGGGCAUUGUGGUGGGGACCGUCUUGAUCAUCCGAGGCCUGCGUUCAGUUGGUGCUUCCAGACACCAAGGGCCCUUGUGAAUCCCAUCCUGAAAAGGAAGGUGCAUCACCAUCUACAGCAGCGGAAGAGUGGACUUGCUACAUGACCUAGCACUAUUCUCUGGCCCGAUUUAUCAUACCCUUUUUCUCCUGCAAAUGUUUCUCCUCUUACCUUUUCUCUGCUUUUUUUUUCUUAAGCUUCUGUAUCCCCUCAGAGCUCACAAAUGCCUUUGAAUUCUUUCCCUGACCUCCUGAUUUUUUUUUCUUUUCUCAGGUGUUACCUACUAAGAGAUGCCUGGGGUAAGCCGCCCAGCUACCUAAUUCCUCAGUAACAUCGAUCUAAAAUCUCCAUGGAAGCAAUAAAUUCCCUUUAAGAGAUCUAUGUCAAAUUUUUCUAUCUUUCAUCCGGGGCUGACUGAACCUAUGGCUAAGAAUUGUGACACUCUCAUGUUUCAAGCCAAUUUCAUCUCAUUUCCCAGAUCAUAUUUCAUAUCCAGUAACACAGAAGCAACCAAGUACAAUAUAGCCUGAUAAUAUGUUGAUUUCUUAGCUGACAUUAAUAUUUCUUUCUUCUUUGUGUUCUCACCCUUGGCACUGCCGCCCAUCCCUCAAUUCAGGCAACAAUGAAGUUAAUGGAUACUCUCUGCCCUUUGCUCAGAAUUGUUAUAGCAAAAAUUUUAAAACCAAAAAAUAAGUUUGUACUAAUUUCAAUAUGGCUUUUAAAAGUAUGAUGGAGAAAUAAAUUAGGAUAAAGGAACUUUGAAUCACAAAAAUAUCAAAAGUAAAAAUUUAUUCUCAAAA